CUUUUUCGUCUGGGCUGCCAACAUGCCAUCCAGACUGAGGAAGACCCGGAAACUUAGGGGCCACGUGAGCCACGGCCACGGCCGCAUAGGCAAGCACCGGAAGCACCCCGGCGGCCGCGGUAAUGCUGGUGGUCUGCAUCACCACCGGAUCAACUUCGACAAAUACCACCCAGGCUACUUUGGGAAAGUUGGUAUGAAGCAUUACCACUUAAAGAGGAACCAGAGCUUCUGCCCAACUGUCAACCUUGACAAAUUGUGGACUUUGGUCAGUGAACAGACACGGGUGAAUGCUGCUAAAAACAAGACUGGGGCUGCUCCCAUCAUUGAUGUGGUGCGAUCGGGCUACUACAAAGUUCUGGGAAAGGGAAAGCUCCCAAAGCAGCCUGUCAUCGUGAAGGCCAAAUUCUUCAGCAGAAGAGCUGAGGAGAAGAUUAAGAGUGUUGGGGGGGCCUGUGUCCUGGUGGCUUGAAGCCACAUGGAGGGAGUUUCAUUAAAUGCUAACUACUUUUUCCUUGUGGUGUGAGUGUAGGUUCUUCAGUGGCACCUCUACAUCCUGUGUGCAUUGGGAGCCCAGGUUCUAGUACUUAGGGUAUGAAGACAUGGGGUCCUCUCCUGACUUCCCUCAAAUAUAUGGUAAACGUAAGACCAACACAGACGUUGGCCAGUUAAACAUUUCUGUUUAUAAAGUCAGAAUAAUACCUGUUGAUCACUGAAAGGCCUGCAUGUAUUGUACUCUGAAUUUUACAGUGAAUGAGAGAAUGUACCCUAAUUGUUCAACAGGGCUCAAAAGGAAAGAUUCCAUUUUGAUGGGUCACAUUCUAAAGAGGGGCAGUGUGAUAGGAAUGAGAUGGUCCUUUAGGACUUAAGUUCUCAGCCCAAGGUUUUUCCACGUGGCCCCCUCAUCUUUUUUUUUUUUUUAAACGGAGUCUCUCUUGCCAGGCUGGAGUGCAGUGGCACGAUCUCGGCUCACUGCAGCCUCCGCCUCCCAGGUUAAGCGAUUCUCCUGCCUCAGCUUCCUGACUAACUGGGAUUACAGGCGCCCACCACCAUGCCCAGCUAAUUUUUGUAUUUUCAGUAGAGAUGGGGUUUCACCAUGUUGGCCAUGCUGGUCUCUAACUCCUAACCUCAAGUGAUCUGCCCACAUCGGCCUCCAAAAGUUCUGGGAUUAUAGUGUGAGCCACUGCGCCCGGCCAUGGCUCCUUAAUCUUGAUCCAAAUUAUUGUUACAUCCAGAAUGUGAUGAAUCAAAAUCUCGAGAUGGGGGUCCAGCAAUCUGAAAUUUCAGUAUGCCAGGGCUUUUCUGUAUGUCAAAGUGGGUUUGAAAUAGUUAAUUUUUCUUCUAGUCUGAAAUGUAUCGGGAAAAUUUGGAAAUCCUGAAGGCUGGAAAUUGAAAUAAGUUUUUCUAGGAUUUGUGUCUCUUGCUAUUGGAAAACUGAUGGUGACCAAUUCAUGUUUACAAAUAAGAUCCUCAUAGAUCUCGGUAAAUUAUAAUUUGCUACAGUUUUAUGGUUCUUCCUGUGAUUUUGAGCUUUUUUUGACCCAAAAUAAUACAGUCUAAAACUAUAGACAAAUAAGAUGGCACUUAGACUCCUGGGUUUUAGUUAGUGGAGGUUUCCUUAGUGCACUGUGGGGUCAUAAUAAGCCGAGAACCAUGGCUGUCUAUGGGACACAUCUGUCAGGACAACCUUUAGAGGAUGUUGGGGAUCAAAUAGAAGGCACAGAGAAGCACUGAAUUGGCUUACAUAAGAAUAGGCUAGAAUUACAAGUAGUGAAACCUCGAUUCAGCUGGACAAUUUUAAACAAAUGUAUCAUUUGGCUUGUAUCUUCUGUUGUGCUGGAGAAGUUAGAAAUAAGGGCUCUCCAGACCAGCCUGACCAACCUGGAGAAACCUUGUCUCUACUAAAUACACAAAAUUAGCCAGGCGUGGUGGCACAUGCCUGUAAUCCCAGCUACUUUGGAGGCUGAGCCAGGAGAAUCUCCAGGAGGCGGAGGUUGCUGUGAGCCGAGAUCGUGCCAUUGCACUCCAGCUUGGGCAACAAGAGUGAAACUCUGUCCACCCCCCCCAAAAAAAGUAAGGGCUCUCCAUUAGGGCCCAUAGAGGACUUGUAAUAUGGAACCUGAAUCCAAGGAUCCCACAAUAAGUGGUCAGUAGUUCAUGAUGAAUUAAAAGACUCAAUAUUUGGUCUUCACCCAAUACCUGUGUGACUUUUAGUCCUAAUUUCCUCAUCUUUAAAAUUUCAGUGAAAGUGCCUACCUGAGGAUUGUGUAGAUUAAAAUGGAAACCGUGCACUUAAUUUUUUGUUUUGUUUUGAGACGGAGUCUCGCUCUGUCGCCCAGGCUGGAGUGCAGUGGUGCGAUCUCAGAUCACUGCAAGCUCCGCCUCCUAGGUUCAGACCAUUCUCCUGCCUCAGCUUCCCAAGUAGCUGGGACUACAGGCGCCCGCCACUGCGCCCGGCUAAUUUUUUGCAUUUUUAGUAGAGACAGGGUUUCACCGUGUUAGCCAGGAUGGUCUCGAUCUCCUGAUCUGCCCGCCUCAGCCUCCCAAAGUGCUGGGAUUACAGGCAUGAGCCACCGCGCCCGGCCCAGGCACUUAAUUUUUGUGUUUGACUUAGUAACUUAAGUGCAAACUAUUACGGGAGCAGAUGGAGUCAAUUGGCCUUCAUGUGAUUGUCAGUGGGAAAUUGGUCCAAGCAGAGGGAAUACUGGUUCAGGAAACUGGUUUGGGAAGGUUAGGCAAACGGGAAGUGCUAUGGUGGAGAGAAAGAUUACUCUGGCCGGGCUGUAAAGGACGGCUACAAUGGGAGGCUGAAGGCAGAACCAAGAAAAUGGGAGUGAGUAUGGAAAAGGUACGAUUCAGACGGCAUAAUGGACGGGACUUGGAGACUGAAUUGUAGUGGGCCGACCACAAAAUGAUAAGGCAUGGAAGGAAGUAGAGUUUGGGGGGAAGGAUCCCUAGUCCCUUAAUGGCUACCUUCUUCCCCAGGAGUUGUUAGGCCAUCCGAUCCCCUGGCCUGGGAAAGAAACACUGAUUUCGUUGCUGGCUUGUUCACUCACCAGAAGCUACAGCUACUAACAGUUCUAAAAACUGUUUCAUGUGAUGAGGAACAGACGAAAAUAGUUUUGAGCCCUAAGUCCGCCGAUUCCAGUGCUUUCUUGAACCCGCAUUUACUAAAAUAUUUUCAUGACUGCCAAGCUUUGAAUAGCCUGCUGUGUUCAUGGAGGCUCAUACUGGCGAUCUCUAGUGGCUGGCUAAAGCUUGAAUUGCAAAAGAUCUAAUUUCUGGUCUAAUGUAUAUAUGCCUUAAAUAUAGUUGCGUUCAAACGUGGGAGCUGCAGGUGCAACUUGAUUUUAUGACAAAUGGCUGCCACAUAAUUUGCACAAGCAGUGCUCGUCAAGGGCAGCUAAAUCAGGCGAGCUUUCAAUCAAAAUAAAUGUACUACUAAACCCUACUUAGCGGCUAACUAGCCCAAGAGCAGACAGCCCACGGACGGACUGCAAGUCGGAAGCGCGGGCGGAAGCUGUGCAGCGCCCACCUGGUGGCUCCAUCGGCCGCGUUCAUCAGUCAGCACGACCCGACCUCAGUGGCGUCCUCACAACACAGACCGGACCUUGGGUCUUACCCCGGCACCUGAGAACCACUUCCGGUGAGUAGCUUCUACUUCCGGAGACGAUGACUCCCCCGCGUCCCAGACCGGAAGAAGCCCGGCGGAGACCGGCCUCGCUCGGCCACUUCCGGCAAGGGCGGAGCCGGCCAGUGGUGCGCGAGCGCAGAUAACUCCCCUGGAGAGGCGGGAUGUUCAACUCCACCCCUGGUCCUUGGGCGGCCGUGGGUCCCCUUCGAAGCGGAGGAAUGGCCAACCUCGCCGCACUUCGAGCCCCUUUAGGGUGCGUUUAAGAACAGUGGGCGUGGCCUUUACGUAAAUCUUCGAGAUGGGAACCUCCAGAAUUUGUCUCAAUUGUCUAAAAGGUAAUGAGCGUCAGCGACAUUCAAGGGCACUUUGGGCUAAAAAAGAAAGUGCUUGUACACGGAUGGAAAUAUUCUAGAAGAACAUAAAAGGAAUUUCCUCUUAGGAGGUUAGGGAAAUGAGCACGAAGUAUGUUUUGGUGCAGUUUUUUGUUCAACCCAAUGCGUAUUUUCAUAUUGAGAGGCAAUAUAAAUGGAGCGAAAGUAUCUUGAGAAAAAAAAAAAAACUACCAGAACUUGCCGUUGCUGAAAAGUAAUAUUUUCUCUUUCGAGAGUUUUCAUGGCCUUUUAAAUUACACCCCCACCUCCACAGGCAAAUAAAUUUGUUUUGGAAUGCAUACCACAUCAUCUGGCUCUAGAAACGUAUUUUGUGUAGCUCCCCUAGCAAGAAUAUAGGUUAAAGCGUAAAUUUAAUUCCUGGCUCUAUUUUACAUCCCAAUUUUUAUUUUCCUCUCAUUCCCACUUUACGUUGUUUCAAAUAACCUAGUUUGUGUAUCCCUGUAAGUCAUUUUGGUAUAAAGUAGGUUAUAAGUGUACAUGCGAAAAGAUGUUUUUAACAAAAAUGUAACUGA